AUUGUGGGCAGCUCCCCGCUCUGCCGCUGCCGCCGCCGUCGCCCAAGGAGGAUCGGGGCCGGGCCGGGCCGGGAUGAUCCGGGUCGGAAGGCCGCCGCCGCCGGAGGGAGCGGGUCACCCAACGCCGCACUGAGCCGCCCCCGCCCCGCCCCGGCCCCGGGGGAUGCGCCGCCCCGAGCUGCUGCCUCCGCCGCCGCCGCAGCCGCAGCCGCAGCGGGCACAGAGCAGGUAGAUGGCCCCCUCAGGGCAGGCCCGGCGGACACCCCUCCCUCUGGCUGGCGGAUGCAGUGCCUAGCGGCCGCCCUUAAGGACGAAACCAACAUGAGUGGGGGAGGGGAGCAGGCCGACAUCCUGCCGGCCAACUACGUGGUCAAGGAUCGCUGGAAGGUGCUGAAAAAGAUCGGGGGCGGGGGCUUUGGUGAGAUCUACGAGGCCAUGGACCUGCUGACCAGGGAGAAUGUGGCCCUCAAGGUGGAGUCAGCCCAGCAGCCCAAGCAGGUCCUCAAGAUGGAGGUGGCCGUGCUCAAGAAGUUGCAAGGGAAGGACCAUGUGUGCAGGUUCAUUGGCUGUGGCAGGAACGAGAAGUUUAACUAUGUAGUGAUGCAGCUCCAGGGCCGGAACCUGGCCGACCUGCGCCGUAGCCAGCCGCGAGGCACCUUCACGCUGAGCACCACAUUGCGGCUGGGCAAGCAGAUCUUGGAGUCCAUCGAGGCCAUCCACUCUGUGGGCUUCCUGCACCGUGACAUCAAGCCUUCAAACUUUGCCAUGGGCAGGCUGCCCUCCACCUACAGGAAGUGCUAUAUGCUGGACUUCGGGCUGGCCCGGCAGUACACCAACACCACGGGGGAUGUGCGGCCCCCUCGGAAUGUGGCCGGGUUUCGAGGAACGGUUCGCUAUGCCUCAGUCAAUGCCCACAAGAACCGGGAGAUGGGCCGCCACGACGACCUGUGGUCCCUCUUCUACAUGCUGGUGGAGUUUGCAGUGGGCCAGCUGCCCUGGAGGAAGAUCAAGGACAAGGAACAGGUAGGGAUGAUCAAGGAGAAGUAUGAGCACCGGAUGCUGCUGAAGCACAUGCCGUCAGAGUUCCACCUCUUCCUGGACCACAUUGCCAGCCUCGACUACUUCACCAAGCCCGACUACCAGUUGAUCAUGUCAGUGUUUGAGAACAGCAUGAAGGAGAGGGGCAUUGCCGAGAAUGAGGCCUUUGACUGGGAGAAGGCAGGCACCGAUGCCCUCCUGUCCACGAGCACCUCUACCCCGCCCCAGCAGAACACCCGGCAGACGGCAGCCAUGUUUGGGGUGGUCAAUGUGACGCCAGUGCCUGGGGACCUGCUCCGGGAGAACACCGAGGAUGUGCUACAGGGAGAGCACCUGAGUGACCAGGAGAAUGCACCCCCAAUUCUGCCCGGGAGGCCCUCUGAGGGGCUGGGCCCCAGUCCCCACCUUGUCCCCCACCCCGGGGGUCCUGAGGCUGAAGUCUGGGAGGAGACAGAUGUCAACCGGAACAAACUCCGGAUCAACAUCGGCAAAGUAACUGCCGCCAGGGCGAAGGGCGUGGGUGGCCUUUUCUCUCACCCCCGAUUCCCAGCCUUGUGCCCCUGCCCUGUUCCUCCUAAGCACCCUGUCCCCGGCCAUCUGCCUGCUUGCCCUGCCUCUGUUUCCCGGUCCCUCCCCGCACUAGCCUCGCUGUGUCUUCCAUCAUCAUCAUCCUCUGUCUCCUUCACCCUGAGGAGACCAUCCGCCCACAGCCGCCUCAUCAGCCCCAGCUCAUGGCACUCCCCUCUCCUGCAGAGCCCCUGUGUGGAGGAGGAACAGAGCCGAGGCAUGGGGGUCCCCAGCUCCCCAGUGCGUGCCCCCCCAGACUCCCCCACAACCCCAGUCCGUUCUCUGCGCUACCGGAGGGUGAACAGCCCUGAGUCAGAAAGGCUGUCCACGGCGGACGGGCGAGUGGAGCUACCUGAGAGGAGGUCACGGAUGGAUCUGCCUGGCUCGCCCUCGCGCCAGGCCUGCUCCUCUCAGCCAGCCCAGAUGCUGUCAGUGGACACAGGCCACGCUGACCGACAGGCCAGUGGCCGCAUGGACGUGUCAGCCUCUGUGGAGCAGGAGGCCCUGAGCAACGCCUUCCGCUCGGUGCCGCUGGCUGAGGAGGAGGAUUUCGACAGCAAAGAGUGGGUCAUCAUCGACAAGGAGACGGAGCUCAAGGACUUCCCUCCAGGGGCUGAGCCCAGCACAUCGGGCACCACGGAUGAGGAGCCCGAGGAGCUGCGGCCACUGCCCGAGGAGGGCGAAGAGCGGCGGCGGCUGGGGGCAGAGCCCACCGUCCGGCCCCGGGGACGCAGCAUGCAGGCGCUGGCGGAGGAGGACCUGCAGCAUUUGCCGCCCCAGCCCCUGCCACCCCAGCUGAGCCAGGGCGAUGGCCGUUCCGAGACGUCACAGCCCCCCACGCCUGGCAGCCCUUCCCACUCACCCCUGCACUCGGGACCCCGCCCUCGACGGAGAGAGUCGGACCCCACAGGCCCACAGAGACAGUUGGAGGAGGACAGACUCUCGGGGCACUCCCUCCCGCGGUACAGCCCCCUGCGACGACUGGCGUCCUCCGUGUUCUCCUCCUCCACGCUGGAGACGGAGCAUUACCCUCACCCCGGCGGCGGCGGCUCCUCGGGCUCCUCCGGUUCCCUCAUUCAGCGCAGCCGCUCGGCUGAGAGCAGCCCUGUGCGGGCGCCCCACCGGCGCCACGCGCCCCUCGCUGCUGGCAACCACAGACUCAUGCCCUCGGUGCUCCGCAUCUCGCGGUCCCAGCUGCAGCAGGUGUGGGCCCGGUUCACCCACAAGACCUAGGCUGGGCCCCCCCCCUCCUGGAGGGGGCAGGUGGGGGGGGGUGGGGAGCAGGCAGAGGACCAUGGUUCCUUCCCAGGACGCAAUAAUCACACACUCACACAUCCCAUCCCACCCCAUCAUGCAAUACAGCCCCCCUAGAACGUUGGCCCAAGGUACUGUAAUACUCCCACCCCAAGCAGAGUCUCCGUCCCACCUCCCCAUCAGCUCCCUUUGUAGGUGCCAGCCAAAUGGUGCAGGGAGGGGUGGGGCUGGUGGUACAGUUUCCAGGACAGGGCAGGGGCGCUCAGCUGGAGCCACUGAUGGGUCCAGAGUCCAGUGGAAAGAGAGGUGUCAGGGAGAUGAGGCCUGCAGGGCCAGAGGCACUCUGGUAUGGGCUUUGUUCUGUUUAAUUUGUGAUCUCUUGGCAUGGCUGGGUCUGAUCCACCCCGAGGGGCUGGCGGGAGGCCAAGACCCUCCUUGCAUGGUGUGUGUGUGUGUGUGUGUGUGUGUGUGUGUGUGUGUGUGUGUCCCUGUGUAUGGAUGGAGGCCAGGACAGCCAGGUUUGGAAUGUGGUGGGGAGUGUUUCAAUGCUCAGUGAUCGGGGGAGGAGCCCUGUGACCUAGCGAGACUUUCUCAGGCCAUCAUCAUUGAGGACAGAGUUCUCUCCUCACACAUCUUACCCCAGGAAGGCUCAGUCCAUGGUAGGCUGCCCCUCCCCCAAGACACCUGUGCCAUCACUCCCUGGUAGGAUUGGGUGUCUGUCCUCGGCUCCUCAGGAACUGAGGAUGGAUGAGAGGGGCCUGGGAUCCACCUCCCAAGGCAGGCUGGAACUGAGCAACGAGGAGACCCAGCUUAGAAGCAGUGGCAGCUAAGGUGGUUGUUAAGGAUGACGUGAGAAACCAUGUGCUUGUCAGCAAAACCAGUGUCUCAGGACAAAUCCCAGGCGGGAGCAGCCCCACCUCUGCCCUUCUCAGAAGGUGACUCCUUCCUGUAGGUGCUCGGUCAGCCCCAAGGGCGGUGGUGAAGACACAGCAGAAGAGAGGCAGGUUGGAUAGGGAUCUGGACACUUGGGAGUGGGGAAGUGUCAGGAUGCCAGCUUGCGCCUGCCUCUUCUGCCCAUUUCUCAGCCCCCAACCUUCACUGCAGGGAGCCCAAGUUUCCCUUUAUUCAUCCUGCCCAUGUCAGCCAGCACCUCUGUUCCCCUGGGGAAUGCGGUAGUAGUGAAGUGGGUACUAGAAAGGGCCGUGCCUGUAUGGGGAGGGGAGGAGGCCCAAAGAUUUGCAAAAUGUUUAUUUCAGUGAGACUGUGUCUGUAUGUUUGCUUGUGUGCAUGCGCGUACACUUGUGCAUAAGAGUGUGCUUACGAAUGAGCGUUUGUGCAUGUGGAAGGGCUGCCAUGGAUGAAUGCUCAGGCUGUGCACUGUGUAAUUCCAGGAAGUGCCAUUUACAUAGACCUCAAUGUGACUGGCACGUGCGCAAGUUGCACAGUGCUGUAUGAGUGUGUGUAUGCACAUGUGUGUUAGGGAGCCAGAAAGAUGUCUAUGCAGUCAUUGGUAGUUUCCUAUGUAGCUACUCUCAUCCCAGCUUCACUCUUCUACCCCUCUCUCCCUGUAACCUCUGCUUGGCCCAUCAAUUCCCCAGAUGUCUCUGGUUAGAGUAGAGGCCUCAGGGCCCUGGCCCCUGCCUGGGGGUGCCAUAAGUGUGGUGGGCAGUGCCCUGGAGCCAAACUGUCCACACAGAGGGCCACCAUUGUGGUAUGGCUCAUCCACACCAUUCACAUAAGCCACUCCAUAGUCACACACUCCUUUCCCCAAAAUCUUUCUUUGUAAGUCUAUUUAUUUAUUUAUUUAUUUAUUUAUUUAUUUUUGAGGAUGUCUGGGCCAAGAGCACCUUCUCCAUCUGGCAACAAAAGCCAGAUUUGGGUUCUAAUACUUGUGCCCCACCCCCACCCCCAUCUCAGCUGCUCACUUUUGAAUCUCCCCAAACCCAAGCCUCUGUUGCCCUCUGGGCUGUUUUGGAUGGCUUUGCACCCUGCUCAGGCAGUAGGCAGGAGAGGGUCAAGGUGGACCCUUUGAGAAGGGACAGAAAACAAAAAGCACAAAGGUGAGGGGGUGAGGCUGAACAGUGGCCCCACUCCCCUCCUGCUGGCACUGCCUCCCCCAGCCACCUCCUCUUGCCCUCUUCCCAUCCACCCCAGGUAGUGGCAGGAGGUGAAGUGAAGGGAACCUGCCCACCAUCUGCUCCAUAAGUCAGCAGCAGUGUGGGCAAGGGCCCCCCCACCCAAUCUGGGGUUGGAUGAAACCAAGCACUCUGUGAUCCAGCAUUCCCUUCUAGAGGGUUCCACUACUCAACCCUGAGCACAGCUCCAUCUCAGUGACCAGAACCCUGAGGUACUCUAAGAUCCCAAAGUGCCUUGUGAAAUAUUGAAGAUGAUGGCACUGGCUUCAGCCUCAUUUCAGCAUUACAUACAUAUUACUGUUUCCAACGCCUUUGGAAGUGGGAGAUCCAGCAUUGAGAAGGCGGCUGAGUUUUCAAACACACACCCCCCACCUCAGAACUGACACCUGUGGGAGAGGGUGUGUCCUUUAAAGCAAGGCCAUGGUUCAAAGCAUGUUGUCCUUUAGGGGGACAUCCUUUUGUAUAUCCUCCAUGGUGGAGGGGAGAGUGUUUUGUAAGCCAUAAAGCUCUGAGCUAACAGGUGAUCUUAAUAAUAUUAUCUUUUCGGGGUGGCUUUGACUCUUGGAGAUUGUUAAGGUCAUCUAAGCCACUUGUGUUGGAUUAAGUUCAUGUGAAGCUCGGCAGAGCUUCACAUGGUUUGGGUCGAGUUGCUGGUCUCCGGUUCCCAGGCUAGGUGGGGAUGCUGUGAGCCUGCAAUAUUGUCACUCUUGUUUUCUGAAGCAUUUCCCAAGAGAAGGCCAGAAUGUUUCAAGAUUGAUACCCUGCUUGGGGAAAGCGUGUAGCCUCCUCGGGGUCAGCUUUGAAAAGAGACAGCUGUCUUUGUUGUAUUUUGAAAGUGGUGUUUUCGCACUUCAUAGUCUCACUCUGCAUUUAGUGGUGGCUUACAAUUAUUUGUGAUUUUAUUUAAUAGCCACUGGCACACAGUGCUUAUUAUGUGCCAGGCAGCGAUCUAAGCACUUUACAAAAUUAACUCAUUUAAACCUCAUGAUAGCUUAUGAGGUAGAUCCCAGUAUUAUCUGCAUUCAACAAAUUAAUCAGAACAUUUUAUUUACCAGAACAUAUAAAAAACCCACCCAUGCCGAAUAAUCUGAGGUCUUGUUUGACAGAGUUUGUGAAACAUCUUGGUCUAUGUAUUGGUUGAUUGAUUGUCCUUUGCGGUGGGCCCCCUCCUCAGUCUAUAGAAAAGAGGGGAGUUGUCAGCAAGCCAUAUUUUCCUUCCUUUCCCAUUCCCACCUUGCCAUGGGGUGGCAUCCAGAUGGGAGUCACUCCAGAGUACUGGGGUUGGUUAAAAUGGCUGGACCCUGUCUCUCCAGAGACCUCCAACCCCUCAAUCCCACAUGGCCCCAAGCAUCCCACAGCAGCUCUGGGGAUCAGGUGGGCAGAGGAGGAGUUAGCAUGAGAAAGCAGGGGCUCCAAAGCCUGACCUCAGUGGGAUUGGUGAGGUCCUAGGGGUCAGACUCACAGACGGGGAAGACACUGGCAUCUGUGAACACCGAAUGGGUGUCACCAACUCGUACAUCAACAAGAUCCAAACAGUGUCAGGGAAGUGGCAGGUUCAGGGACUGUGGUAAACAGGGGAACUCCCAUGCCCAUACCAUCCUCAGCUCAACCAAUUGUUGCCACUAUCUUCUAAUUUUUAUUUGAAAUCUCCCAAUUUUUAAUUGUUGGCAUCUAAUUUUAAAAAGAAAAAUCACUGUAUGAACCAAACCAAAAUGGUUUACAGGCAGAGGUGGCCUAAACUCAUUUUGCAACCACUGUGAGCCUGAGGACUUCCUGCACCACCCUCUGUCCAGGGCUGCAGCACUCAAAGGCGACAGUGUUCUUGCCCAGGAACUCGAACCUGGCCAGUGGGGAUGUGUGGUGUGUGCUGUGUUUAUACAUGUGGUGUGCAUAAGUGCCUGAAUGAGUGUGGGGGCCAGUGGACCUUUUUGUGGUGAGUGGGGGCCUCCUGGUGGGACUAGUAUUUUCUCCAUGGGAGAGGGUAUGUUCUGAGGACCCUGGGUCCGUGACAAAUGCGCUAGUAAAUUUUCGAUAACUCAAUAUACAUCCCCCACACACUCAAGGCAGCUUGGGUCACAGCAAUAACCACUGAACACUCAUCCCAACCGCUAACAUCCUGAACCCAACGAUAUCCCUUUGCAUUUCCAGUUUUGGGGAAAACAGACACAGCCCUGCCUAGUGGGUGGGGGAUGGUGGCACCUCUGAGCCAUGCUGGUCCCAGGACACCCGGACUCGCUCUCUCUUCUGUCCUGCCUAGAUCCCUUUUUCUGGGGAGGGGUGGUGCUGUCUUGCUCAGGCAGUGGUCGGGGGAGCCUUGGGCCCCUGGGUAGGCAGAAGGAGCUGUGUAAAUGUAUUUAUAUGGAGUGGGCAGUGGAGGGAACCAUACUUGGGGAGGGUGUGGCUCUGACCGGGGAUGGGGGCAACUCCAGCUGUGUGUGGGGAGCCUGGAAAAUGCUGUAUCCUCUGCUGUCCUUGGGUUGAUGUGGUACUUGGGGAUGGAAGUGUAGAUCUCUCCGGAGGGCCUGAACCCCAUCCCACCCUACCCCAAACUCCACUUAGACCUGGGACACACUCAACUCAAGGGGCAGGAACCAGCCCACCCUCCAUACAGUCAGCCCCUGAAAAUGUCAAGCAUCCUUCUCCCUAAGGGAAGGGCUCCAGGUCUGAGGGCCACAACCCUCCCAUAUCCCUCUGGUUCCCCACACACCAUCCAGUGGGCGUCCCAGCCCAGGAGGCCCCAAGCCUGAGUGCCCGCUUCCUCCAAAUGAGGGGUGGGGAAGGGGUGGAGAGGAGGGGGAAAUGGAGCCCACAGGACUCCUUCCUACAACCUUCCUAGACUCUCCUCCGCUUGGCUCCGCCGUCAGUCCCACCACUCACCCUCCCUCCCUGCACAGGCUGUGGGGGUGCGGGCAGUGGGGUCCACUUGGCCACUCACUAACCGGCCCUCACGCACUCACACUCACACCCACACUCACACACUCUCCCUCCGUAGCUGCGCGCACUUCGCCCACUCUCCGGACCCUGCACUAGCGGCCCCGGCCGGGAGGGCACGAGGACUGCGCAGCCGGACCCCCGCAGGUCCCCAAGCCAGGGGUCCCGUCCAUCCGCCCGCCCCCGCGGCCAGCGCCACGAAUGUACGGCCCGCCCCACACAGCGCCCCGCGGCGCCCUGCACCCCCCGCCGGACUUCGGCCCCGCCGCGCUCCCGCCCCACCCCGCCGCCGAGGCUUCCCCUGGGUUCGCGUCCCCCGCCGCCCCCGUCGCCCCGCCUUCGCGCCCGUUUUCGUUUGCUUUUCCCUGCUGCUGGCUGGCGGCCUUUGGGUCCCUGGCCCCGGGGCGGGGGCGGGCUGGAGUGGGGCUCCCCUCAGUGCUGCCAGGCUGGGGUGCGGAUGGGGACAGGCGGAGGCGUUCGGCUAAGCCUCCAGGCUCGGAGGGCCCUGUCGCCCCACCCCUGACUCCCGUUACCUCACUGCCCGUCGGGCUGCCCCCCACCCCGCCCCAAUAAUUGGCCUUGCAAUUGGAUGCCAAAGAGCCCAGAGUUGAGGGGGAGCAGAGCUUUGAGCCCAGGUCUCUCAGAGCAACCCAACAGCCCCCUUUUUGCCCACGCCCCAAUCCGCGUCCCCUGCCCCACCCCACCACUGAGGGCCCUGGGGGUCACCAAACAUGCCCCCCCAUUUCCAGCUCUUCCCACACCCCCACCCCCGAAAAUAAAACUCAGGGACCAACAUCUGCUUCCUUUGCACUUGCUCCGUCGACCCCGCUCCCCGCUCGGAGGGGCUUCCGUGGGGGAGGGGGCGGGGCUCCGGGCCCUCAGAGUUCUCAGUGUCGAGCGAGGAGAGGGGCUGGCCCCUGCCCCCGGAGAAGCGGGACUGGUAGGAGAGAGAAACUCAGCACCGGGGCCCAGCUGAGCCCCUUCCUGCGUAAGGAGACGCCUUCUAAUUGCGGGGUGGGGGCGGAGUAGGGGAGGGAUAGGAAGGGGAUUAGCGAGAGGACCCUCGCGGAGGUCCUGAGUCCCAGUCGGUUUAUUCCUGAGCCUUCCCCUCCCAUCGUAAGUCCUUCCCUCGACCCCCCAUUUUGUACUGCAAUAAUACUGUAUUAUACGCUUGCACUAUUUCCCGACCCUGGCCAGCGGAAGCAUGCACGAAAAACUCAAAACCACACACACGCUCACACGCACACACACGCACACGAAGAUGGGACGCUUUUUUUCUUCCUCUCUCUCUCCGGGGUGCGUCCUCCUUAGUGUACAUAGCGGCGUCGGGGGGUGGCCCCAGGCCCGGGUAGAAAAGCAUGCACUGAGCCCCCUGCCCCUAGACUGCGAGUACUGUACAAAUCCAACACUUGAAACCGACACGCACACGCGCGGCGCCGCCACGGGGGUGGGACACGGACACGCACCCACGCGCACACGGCCGCGCACGGGCGGGGAGGGGGCGCCCCGCCGUCACGCGUCGCUGUGCGAGGGAUUUUGUGCCUUUUUAAGUCCCUGUAUGUUAAUGCAGACAAUCCGGAGAGCUUGUGUACUACCAAAUCCUGAUUAAAGACGCCUUCCAGGAA